CUCUUCUCUUGAAGCAGAUGCGAAGGCUCCCCGAAUGAGAAAGAAUACUCGGAAUCAGCGGUGAAUUGCAGUGAUCUUUCAGAGAAAGCGCCUGUUCAACUUUGUCCUCUCUCAGAGACUCAGAGCCUUGGGGCACUGAGGGAUGCCAGUUCUGCCUGUUCAUCUGGAACCUGGAUCUAAGGAGGGAAGAGGCGUUGCCCCUGCUGGCAUAGUCAGGUACCAGCCCAGCCAGGUAAGAACCUAAAGUCCUUGUUGCUUUGUGAUUUUCCCUUCAUCUAGAGAGGAGGCCUUUGGAGAACAGGUCUUGUGGGUGCUUUGUCAGAGACUAGAAGCCGAGAACAUCCCUUUUCAGAGCUCUGGGUUUUCUGUUCCUCAUGCAACCUCUGCAGUUGGGAUGAAUAAUAUAUUUUAAUUUUAUUUUACAAUAGGGAAACUGACAAAUAUUGAAUUCCUGAACUGAGCAAUCUUGGCCUGUAGGCCCAUGAACUUGGAGAAAAAAUUAAAUCUUUAUUUUUAUUAACCUUUAACUCAAAUUUAGCAUUUUCUUAAAAUAUGGAUAUAGGCAAGAAACCACAGUAGAAUCAGCAGAACUUGUGACUUUGUCACCAACAGAAAUCACAGAUAUUUUCAUACCACAUGAUAUGUUGUAGCUAUCUCAAGACAUUGUUUCUAUUCAUCACUACUUUGAAAUUCUGGGAGUCCUUAGAUCACUGCUAGAUCUUAAUAUUUCAUGCAUCAAGGAACACAUAUAUUACUAUAUUACAAUUUUUAAAUAUUUCAGUAUAAUCAAUUUCUUCCUAUGUAACACAGCAUACCUUAUUUUAUGCGUUUAAAUACGUAGGCUUCACCAGACUACCAAAGAUUAAGAAAAAGGUUAAGAACCUUUGCUUAAAGGAAAUGCUACCUUAGAGCUCUGUUAGCCUCUCAUUCACUAAUUUGCCAUGGAUCAUAAAUUAAUAUAAUGCAGAUUUUUUUUGAAGCCUAGCAAAGGAAGUUUAGCUUUUAAAGCAUUGAAAGGACGUCUUAUCACUAAGGGAUUCCCAUAGAUUUAAUAACAAAAAUGGUACUAUAGGAAGUAUAUUGAUUUGAUCUUCUGCAUUUUCUGGAUAAAAGGAUGUAUGCAGAACCUUUCAGCUGUCAUUAAACAAAAACAAGAGCUAAUGCAUAAGGCAGCUCAUGAAACUUAUUCAAGACUGUAAAUAAUUGAUAGGCUGAGCUUGUGGUGGUGCUGCUUCAUACAUCCUUAAUUGAUUAAACAUUUUUUGAGUGUUGAAGUUAAUGGUAAAAAUAAUAGCCAACAGUUGGGAAUGUCAUUUUUCCAGUAUUUCUUCAAUUAGGGUAAUGUACAUUAAACACAGACUUUUACGUCCUCUGACCACUAAAGUUAUGGAAUCCAUAUUAGGAAAAUUCAAGUUUGGAAGUUUGAGGCUUUUAGAAAUAUGAGAAGUGUUAUUUAAGCAAAUUUAAAAUUUUACAUUAUCACCGCGAGCAGAAAAUGCAAGGGUUUGUGUAGAAUAUUUUGUCUUUUUGGAAGUAAUGCUGCAGAGAUACUUAAGCCAAGAAAAAUGUUGCCAUUUUUUGUUUUCUUUUCUGCAGGUAUUGAACGGGCUGAGCUUUUCAUGAUGGUUCCUGCUGACCUGGAAACAUCUUAAAUGGAAGGUUAGCUUCUAUGAGUCACUGAUACUCUUUUUAUUGCUAUUUCUAAAUUUCCUUGGCUUGAAAAUUACUUCUGCUUUGCAGAAAUUAUCUGCUUGCAGCUGUGGAUAAUUUAUAACAAUCUCUGGUGAAACCUCAGAAAAGAGAUAUGCUUUUGUCUUAGAUGGAUGUCAGCAGCUGCUGCAGAACCCGGUGAAAACACCCCCCGGGUAGCACGAGGCUCUGCGAGCCGUAACUCCGACAAACGCAGAACUUCUUGAGGCUUUCUUCUUCUAAGGAGUAUGACACAGUUAAAAAGGAAAAAAGAACCACAAGCAAAACAGUUGCCAGUGAAAUAGGAGAGGGAGCUCUUUAAACAAGGCUGGCUGCAGCUGGCCUCCGCCGCUCAUCUGCAGGGCGUGAGCGCUUGGUCCAUGCAGUGAAGCUCUUCCAACCUGGGUCAACGAAAACGGAGAAGAAAUGGCCCAAGAAAUAGAUCUGAGUGCUCUCAAGGAGUUAGAACGCGAGGCCAUUCUCCAGGUCCUGUACCGAGACCAGGCGGUUCAAAACACAGAGGAGGAGAGGACACGGAAACUGAAAACACACCUGCAGCAUCUCCGGUGGAAAGGAGCGAAGAACACGGACUGGGAGCACAAAGAGAAGUGCUGUGCGCGCUGCCAGCAGGUGCUGGGGUUCCUGCUGCACCGGGGCGCCGUGUGCCGGGGCUGCAGCCACCGCGUGUGUGCCCAGUGCCGAGUGUUCCUGAGGGGGACCCAUGCCUGGAAGUGCACGGUGUGCUUCGAGGACAGGAAUGUCAAAAUAAAAACUGGAGAAUGGUUCUAUGAGGAACGAGCCAAGAAAUUUCCAACUGGAGGCAAACAUGAGACAGUUGGAGGGCAGCUCUUGCAAUCUUAUCAGAAGCUGAGCAAAAUUUCUGUGGUUCCUCCUACUCCACCUCCUGUCAGCGAGAGCCAGUGCAGCCGCAGUCCUGGCAGGUUACAGGAAUUUGGUCAGUUUAGAGGAUUUAAUAAGUCCGUGGAAAAUUUGUUUCUGUCUCUUGCUACCCACGUGAAAAAGCUCUCCAAAUCCCAGAAUGAUAUGACUUCUGAGAAGCAUCUUCUCGCCACGGGCCCCAGGCAGUGUGUGGGACAGACAGAGAGACGGAGCCAGUCUGACACUGCGGUCAACGUCACCACCAGGAAGGUCAGUGCACCAGAUAUUCUGAAACCUCUCAAUCAAGAGGAUCCCAAAUGCUCUACUAACCCUAUUUUGAAGCAACAGAAUCUCCCAUCCAGUCCGGCACCCAGUACCAUAUUCUCUGGAGGUUUUAGACACGGAAGUUUAAUUAGCAUUGACAGCACCUGUACAGAGAUGGGCAAUUUUGACAAUGCUAAUGUCACUGGAGAAAUAGAAUUUGCCAUUCAUUAUUGCUUCAAAACCCAUUCUUUAGAAAUAUGCAUCAAGGCCUGUAAGAACCUUGCCUAUGGAGAAGAAAAGAAGAAAAAGUGCAAUCCGUAUGUGAAGACCUACCUGUUGCCCGACAGAUCCUCCCAGGGAAAGCGCAAGACUGGAGUCCAAAGGAACACCGUGGACCCGACCUUUCAGGAGACCUUGAAGUAUCAGGUGGCCCCUGCCCAGCUGGUGACCCGGCAGCUGCAGGUCUCGGUGUGGCAUCUGGGCACGCUGGCCCGGAGAGUGUUUCUUGGAGAAGUGAUCAUUCCUCUGGCCACGUGGGACUUUGAAGACAGCACAACACAGUCCUUCCGCUGGCAUCCGCUCCGGGCCAAGGCGGAGAAAUACGAAGACAGCGUUCCUCAGAGUAAUGGAGAGCUCACAGUCCGGGCUAAGCUGGUUCUCCCUUCACGGCCCAGAAAACUCCAAGAGGCUCAAGAAGGGACAGAUCAGCCAUCACUUCAUGGUCAACUUUGUUUGGUAGUGCUAGGAGCCAAGAAUUUACCUGUGCGGCCAGAUGGCACCUUGAACUCAUUUGUUAAGGGCUGUCUCACUCUGCCAGACCAACAAAAACUGAGACUGAAGUCGCCAGUCCUGAGGAAGCAGGCUUGCCCCCAGUGGAAACACUCAUUUGUCUUCAGUGGCGUAACCCCAGCUCAGCUGAGGCAGUCAAGCUUGGAGUUAACUGUCUGGGAUCAGGCCCUCUUUGGAAUGAACGACCGCUUGCUUGGAGGAACCAGACUUGGUUCAAAGGGAGACACAGCUGUUGGCGGGGAUGCAUGCUCACUAUCGAAGCUCCAGUGGCAGAAAGUCCUUUCCAGCCCCAAUCUAUGGACAGACAUGACUCUUGUCCUGCACUGACAUGAAGGCCUCAAGGUUCCAGGUUGCAGCAGGCGUGAGGCACUGUGCGUCUGCAGAGGGGCUACGAACCAGGUGCAGGGUCCCAGCUGGAGACCCCUUUGACCUUGAGCAGUCUCCAUCUGCGGCCCUGUCCCAUGGCUUAACCGCCUAUUGGUAUCUGUGUAUAUUUACGUUAAACACAAUUAUGUUACCUAAGCCUCUGGUGGGUUAUCUCCUCUUUGAGAUGUAGAAAAUGGCCAGAUUUUAAUAAACGUUGUUACCCAUGUC